GUCUCUGCAGCCGGAGCUCCAGGUCUUGUCUUCACUGCUGUGUGUCCUCUGCUCCUAGAGGCCCAGCCUCUGUGGCCCUGUGUCCUGCAGGUAUUGGGAGAUCCACAGCUAAGACGCCCGGGAGCCCCUGGAAGCCUAGAAAUGGGGCCAUUGCAAUUUAGAGACGUGGCCAUAGAAUUCUCUCUGGAGGAGUGGCAUUGCCUGGACACUGCACAGCGGAAUUUAUAUAGGAAUGUGAUGUUAGAGAACUACAGAAACCUGGUCUUCCUUGGUAUUGUUGUCUCUAAGCCAGACCUCAUCACCUGUCUGGAGCAAGGAAAAAAACCUUUGACCAUGAAGAAACAUGAGAUGGUAGCCAACCCCUCAGUUACGUGUUCUCAUUUUGCCCGAGAUCUUUGGCCAGAGCAGAGCAUAAAAGAUUCUUUCCAAAAAGUGACACUGAGAAGAUAUGAAAACUAUGGACAUGACAAUUUACAGUUUAAAAAGGGCUGUGAAAGUGUAGAUGAGUGUAAGGUGCACAAAAGAGGUUAUAAUGGACUUAACCAAUAUUUGACAACUACUCAAAGCAAAAUAUUUCAGUGUGAUAAAUAUGUGAAAGUCAUUCAUAAAUUUUCAAAUUCAAACAGACAUAAGAUAAGACAUACUGGAAAAAAACCUUUCAAAUGUAUAGAAUGUGGCAAAGCUUUUAACCAGUCUUCAACCCUUACUACACAUAAGAAAAUUCAUACUGGGGAGAAACCCUUCAAAUGUGAAGAAUGUGGCAAAGCCUUCAACUGGUCCUCACACCUUACUACACAUAAGAGAAUUCAUACUGGAGAGAAACGGUACAAAUGUGAAGACUGUGGCAAAGCCUUUAGCCGGUUUUCAUACCUUACUGCACAUAAGAUAAUUCAUAGUGGAGAGAAACCCUACAAAUGUGAAGAAUGUGGCAAGGCCUUUAAGCGCUCCUCUAACCUUACUACACAUAAGAUAAUUCAUACUGGAGAGAAACCCUACAAAUGUGAAGAAUGUGGCAAGGCCUUUAAGCGCUCCUCUAUCCUUACUGCGCAUAAGAUAAUUCAUAGCGGAGAGAAACCCUACAAAUGUGAAGAAUGUGGCAAAGCCUUUAAGCACCCCUCUGUCCUUACUACACAUAAAAGAAUUCAUACUGGAGAGAAACCCUACAAAUGUGAAGAAUGUGGCAGAGCCUUUAAGUACUUCUCAUCCCUUACUACACACAAGAUAAUUCAUAGUGGAGAGAAACCCUACAAAUGUGAAGAAUGUGGCAAAGCCUUCAACUGGUCCUCACACCUUACUACACAUAAGAGAAUUCAUACUGGAGAGAAACCCUACAAAUGUGAAGAAUGUGGCGAAGCCUUUAAGUACUCCUCUUCCCUUACUACACAUAAGAUAAUCCAUACUGGACAGCAACCCUUCAAGUGUGAAGAAUGUGGCAAGGCCUUUAAGUGCUUCUCUAUCCUUACUACACAUAAGAGAAUUCAUACUGGAGAGAAACCCUACAAAUGUGAAGAAUGUGGCAAAGCCUUCAACUCGUCCUCACACCUUACUGCACAUAAGAGAAUUCAUACUGGAGAGAAACCCUACAAAUGUGAACGAUGUGGCAAGGCUUUUAAGCGCUCCUUUAUCCUUACUAGACAUAAGAGAAUUCAUACUGGAGAGAAACCCUACAAAUGUGAAGAAUGUGGCAAAGGCUUUAAGUGCCCCUCUACCCUUACUACACAUAAGGUAAUUCAUACUGGAGAGAAACUAUAAAUGUGAGGAAUGUGGCAAAGCUUUAAGCUAUCCCACUAUGCUUUUUUCACAUAAGAAAAUUCAUAUUGGAGGGAAACUGUACAAGUGUGAUAAAUGUGGCAAAGCCUUUAUUUCAUCCUCAAACCUUAGUAGACAUUAGAUAAUUCAUGCGGGAAAGAAACCCAACAAAUAAGAAAAUGCAGCAAAGCCUUUAAGGACACCUCUGCCCUUACUAGACAUAAGAUAAUUCGUACUGGAGAGAAACCCUGUGAGUUUGAUGAAUGUCGGAAAGCCUUUAACCAGCUAUCAACUUUUACUAAAUAUGAGAAUUUAUAUGGAACAUAAACCCUACAAAUAUAAAGAAUGUGACAACGCUUUUAGGAAGUUCUGAACCCUUCUUACACAUAAUUCAUGCUGGACAAAAAUCCUACAAGUUUGAGGAAUGUGGCAAAUCCUAUAACAAGUUUUCAAUAUUUUUUUUUUUGAGAUGAAGUUUCAUGCUUGUCAUCCAAGCUGGAGUACAGUGCCAUGAUCUCGGCUCACUGCAACCUCUGCCUCCUGGGUUUAAGCCAUUCUCCUACCUCAGCUUCCUGAGUAGCUGGGAUUACAGGUGUCCUCCAACAUGCCCAGCUAAUUUUUUUAUUUUUAGUAGAGAUGCGACUUCGCCAUGUUUGCCAGGCUGGUCUCGAACUCCUGACCUCAGGUGAUCCACCCACCUUGGCCUCCUAAAGUGCUGGGAUUACAGGCGUGAGCCACGACGCCCAGCCACAAGUUCUCAAUUCUUAAGAGGCAUGGCAAUAAUUCAUGUUGAAGAGGAAAUCCGCAAAGCUAAAAAAUGUGACAUUGCUUUUACGAACACCUCCAACUUCUCUACACAUAACAAUAAUUAUACUAGUGUGAAACCCUAGAAAUAUAUAAAAUGUGACAAAGCCUUUAUAUGGUUGCCACUCUUGAUUGUAGGUUGGAUAAUUCAUACUGGCAAAACUCCUACAAGUGUGAAGAAUGUGGCAAAACUUUUAAUCAGUUCUUACACCUUAUCUCACAGAAAAGCUAGUAUCCUUGAGAAAAAUUGUACAAAUAGAAGGAAUAUGGAAAACCUAUUAAUUCCUACUCACAUCUAACUCAACAUAAAAAUCUUCCUUUUAAUAAAAGCAUUAAAAUGGCAAUUACUGUCAAAACUUUCAGCAAGUAUAAGCCUUUAAAGUGAAGAAGAGUAUUUAUUGUGAAGACAAGCAUUACAAAUAUAAAGGGAGUUACAUAGUACAUUUACUAGUAUCACAGAUCUUAUUGCACACAUUUUGUACUGGAGGAAAAUCCUAAAGCAGUUGCUCAAGUUUGUUCAACAUCAGGGAAUUUAUAUUGGAGAUGAGUCCUACAAAUGUAUUAAGUUUAGAAACACUUUUUUUUCCCCAGAAACUACAGCUUAGAAAACAACAGAGAGUUUAUGCUAAAAUAUAAUUUUGCAGAUGCAGUAAAUAUUAAAAAAUAUUUAAUUCAAAAUAGAUUGUAUAUAAAUAUCAAGAGAGUUUACAGUAGAAUAACUAAGGCCCCGACACUUCAGACAUUACACUAAAUCAGAGCAUUGAAUAUAAAAACUAAUCCACAACUGCAGUUUUUAGGUAAAUGAUUUCUAUUUAACUUUAAAAGGAGUAGAUUUUUGGAAGCAUUGUAAUUACGUUGAAAGUAUACUUGUUUCCUUGAAUAAAAUUUUUUGAAAGCUGAAUAAUGAUGUAAUACAGCUUUCAAAUUAUGCUGUUAUUUUAUUUCUAUUCACAUGUGAGAAAGCAUGUGAUCAGUGGCUUCUGCAUCAGAGAUAUUCGAUUUUUUUACAUUAUUUGGACAUUAUGACUUUUUCUAUAAAAUAGUAAGAACAUUAAAAUGUAAGACGCAUAAUGAAAAUACAAGUGGAGAAGCUGUUUGUAGUAAAAUUCUAUUAAGUAAUGUAUAACGUAAAUGUUCAGAGCAAUACUUUAUUAUAGUGACACAAAGAAAUAAUUAAAAGUAUAUUAAAAUAAAUGAGUAUAUUACUUUACUACUUGUACUUUUAUGUAAUAAAAUGCAGUGCAUUUUAAAACUGUUAGGGCCGGGCUUGAUGGCUCAUGCCUGUAAUUUCAGCACUUUGGGAGGCCAAGGUGGGCAGAUCACCUGAGGUCAGGAGUUCGAGACCAGCCUGACCAACAUGGAGAAACCCAGUCUCUACUAAAAAUACAAAAAAAAUUAGCCAGGCAUGGUGGUGCAUGCCUGUAAUCUCAGCUACUCAGGAGGCUGAGGCAGGAGAAACACUUGAACCUGGGAGGCAGAGGUUGCAGUGGGGCAAGAUUGUGCGAUUGCACUCCAGUCUGGGCAACAAGAGCAAAACUCUGUCUCAAAAAAAAAAAAGUUUGUUAGAUUAUUUGUGAACUUAAUUUUAUUUUAUUUUUACCAUGGUAAGACUACCGUGCGUUUAAUGAACCAUUAUUGUGCCACUAACUGUAUCCCACUUUACUCAAGGGUGUAGGUACAAUAUUGUAGGAAUAUACUAUUUCAUACAUUGUAAAAUAACAUCUUUAGUAAUCACUGUCAGUGGCUUUAAACUGCAAAUGAGUUAAAUAUUGUUCCCAUAGAUUAAAUUUUGACUCUUUAUUAUUUAAAUUUUUUAUUUGUAUUCGUGGGUAUAUAAUAUGUGUAUAUAUUUAUGCCUUAUAUGGCAUCUUUUGACUCAGGCCUACAAUAUGUAGUAAUUACAUUAUGGUAAAUAAGGUAUCCAUCACCUCUAGCAUUUAUCUUUUGUAUUACCAAUAGUGUAAUUAUAUGCUUUUAUUCAUUUUAAAAUGUACAAUUAAAUUGUUAUUGACUACAGAAUUAUUUCUAUGAUCAUAAUAAUUAUACAAAAAUGUAAAUAAAAUACGGCCAGGCACAGUGGCUCACAUCUGUAAUUCCAGCACUUUGGGAGGCCGAGACAGGUGGAAUGCUUGAGGUUAGGAGUUCAAGGCCAGCCUGGCCAACGUGGUGAAACCUUGUCUCUACUAAAAACACAAAAAUUAGGCAUGGUGGCACAUGCCAGGAGGCUGAGGCAGGAGAAUCGUUUGAGCCCAGGAGGCAGAGGUUGCAGUGAGCUGAGAUCAUGCCACUGCACUCCAGCCUGGCUGACAGAGUGAGUCUCCAUCUCAAAAAAUAAAAUAAAAAUAAAAUCCAUACAUUUCUGAGUCCUGAAAAAUUAUAAAUACUUGUAAUAUAGUUUUCCUUGAACAUGUGGUCUCUGCCUGCAAACACAUAGACUUUUAGUUUUAAUUUACAUAGAGUUAAAUAUACACAUAUUACUCUGAAGAUAAACCUGAGGUGUAAGAAAAUUAUGAAUUGAGUGUUUUUGUGUGAGUAUAGGUUUGUACAUAUUUUCAGAAUAAAAGCAAUUACUGCAACAAAACAAAUUAUGUUAUUUAGGUGAUUAACAAAACUAAACACUUUUAAAAUGGUGAAAGCAAAUCUAUACUUUCUGCUUUGUAUUGAAUUUAUUAAUAUAAAAUGUUCUGGCCUGUGAUUCGGAUUCUCCCCAGAGUCUGCCUAUUAAAGCACAGGCAACUUUGUCUCCAGAAACAACUCUCUUGAGUACAAUAAUAAAAGCCCUCUUAAAACAGGAAAAAAAAAUCAUUUUUAACACUUAUUUGAAUGAACAUUCAACCAAAAUUGAAUAAUUGGAUAUAUUUUUAUUGUUCUAUGUGUGUGUGAAUGUAUAAAUGGUGCAUAAAAAAUAAUUUAAGCCAGAAAAAUAGUUAUUUGUAAUGAAUAAAACUAAAAAGUAGUUAAUUAUUAUAUCCAGUUGAUAUCUUUGUUUAUGUAGAUAACAAAAGCAGCAGAAAGACUCUUUUUUUUUUUCCAUGAUGGAGUGUUGCUCUGUCUUCCAGGCUGGAGAGCAGUGGCGUGAUCUCAGCUCAUGGCAACCUCCACCUCCUGGGUUCAAGCAAUUCUCCUGCCUCAGCCUCCUAAGUAGCUGGGAUUACAGGCAUGCACCACCACGUCUGACUAAUUUUUGUAUUUUUAGUAGAGACAGGGUUUCAUCAUGUUGGCCAGGCUGGUCCCAAACUCCUGGCCUCAUGAUCUGCCUGCUUCAGCCUCCCACGGUGCUGGUAUUAGAAUCAUGAGCCACCGUGCCCAGCAAAAGAUGAUUUUAAACAUUUAUUUAGGUGGGUAGGCAACAUUCUAAGAUAAUACCCUGGAUUACCAGUCUGUUGCACACGUGCUGUGUCAUACUUUCCUCUUGAGUGUAAAAAAAAUGUGUGACUGUGGUGGGAAAUCACUUAUGAAAUUAGGUUACUCAUCCGUAGACUUUGUGUUUAUCAAAAUGGAGAUUAUCCUGAUUGUGCUAAACUUAAUCAGAGGUGCUUUUAAGAGAAAGAGACACAUCACAGAAAAACACCCCUGCUGGCCUGAAAGUAAGUGACUUCUAGGUAGAACAUGUUGUAAGCUGCUUAUGGUGGCCACAUGGCGGGAAAAAUGUUUGUAUCUUGCCAUCAUUUCUGCCUCCUCCAUGUUGCUUCCAGUAAGGAACAUAAGAGGAUUCUAUGGCAGAGGGAAAAAAAAGGGAAUCUCAUUCAUUCAAGAAAUAAUCACCUCUCAUCUGGGAUAGCUUAAGAGAAACAGGAGACCACAACAGGUCCACAUUAAUGGGAGGAAAAAGGUAACCUGGGUAAAAGUGCUCACUGGCAUUAUGGAACAGUAUUUAGUAAGCUGUAGUGAAUGAUCAGCCUCUGGGAUACCAAUAGUCUACCAACAAGGCUGAACUCAUUCUAAUUCAAUCAGCAUGUCUGCACCAUUCUGGUGACACAGGUUUACACUAUUUAUUACAGAAAUGCCAUGAAGACCAGUGGGUAAUGUCCUAAAAUUGAACUUACUUCAAAAAGUAUACCUAAUUGUCUGUUUUCAUAUUUGAAAAACCUUAAAAACAAUGAAUUUAUAAAUAAUUAACUUCUAAUUAUAGAGGAUUCUACUAUACUGUAAUACAAGAUUAAACUGUAAACACAUUAAUAUGAAUAUUUUUUGAAUCCAUGAUUAGUUAUGUAGAUAGUUUCUUUUAGAUUCACAUGACCAAGGUAACAUUAGAGAAAACAUUUGAAAUGGAAUAAAAUUUACCAAGACCACAUUUUUUCAAUGGCUUCGCAUAAUUGCCGUACUUACAGAAAUGGCCAGAUGACUAACAAGAAACAAAGGCAAGAUUUAAGCUUUGCUCAAUGAUUGUUUUUGACCUUUUGAAAUCUGAAAUCCUGGCUAAAGUAUUCAAAGGGAGUAUUUUAUAGGGGCUUCCCAGGGUUUCCAAGUAAUUGAAGAAAGAAUUUCUUUUUUUUUUUUUUAGAAGGAUUCUCACUCUGUCACUCACGCUGCACUGCAAUGGUACGUGCUCAGCUCACUGCAACCUCCACCUCCCUGGUUCAAGUGAUUCUUCCGCCUCAGCCUCCUGAGUAGCUGGGAUAACAGGCACCCGCCAUUAUGCCCGGAUAAUUUUUGUAGUAGAGAUGGGAUUUCAUCAUGUUAGCCAGGCUUGUCUUGAACUCCUGACCUCAGGUGAUCCAUCCACCUCAGCCUCCCAGAGUGCUGGGAUUACAGGCAUGAGCCACUUUUCCCAGCCAGAAUAAUUUUGGUAGGCAGGAAAAUGCACAUUAUGUACACACAUUGCUCUUCUCUGAUUUGCUUUAACACUGAAAAACUGAAGAUUGUAAAUGUAGUCUCAAUUUAGAGUGAAUUAACAAAAGAUUUGUUUUUCAAAAAAGCAAAUGUAUAAAAUUAAUGGGUAACAGAUGCCAUUAGUUGCUAAAAAAUAGUAUGACUAAAGUUGGUAAUUAUCUAGCUAUGCAAAUAACAGCCCAAUUAAAUUAAGACUCUAUUGGGUGCAUGUGGAAAGCAUUGAUGUGCAGUGUGGUGCCUCCACUCAGCAUUUCCUUACUGUCUCUUUACAGAGAUACCAAUUCCCCCUGAAUUACUCAGGGUCCAUAAUGGUUUUAGAAAUGUUUGUUCUCUGGAGCUGUAAAGAAAUAGCACUUGAAAAUAAAUUUAAUUUUUCUUAGCAAGGCCAUUUUUACUUUUUGCAGAAAGCAGUUUUGCCACGAGUACACUGAACAGAGGAGACAGAGUCAUUUAUAACUUGACGUGUCCACCCUACUGCUGUGUCUGGUUUUCAUUGGCUGGAAUGGGACCUCACAUUCUGUAUGUCCCAAUUGUUUAGCAACUUAGAACUUUUUAAAAGAGACAAAGGCAGAGGAGAACAAAGGAAGGAGGAAGUAACUUGUGGAAUGCUGAGAAAGGUAAAAAUACCUUCAAAUAAGGAGGAGGAACAGGCUAUGACCUAAUGCUUGCUUGGAUUAGUAUAAGCAUGCCAGGGCAAAUAUUUAGGCUAAAUUGUGGGAGCUAAGAACAUAAAGUACAUUGAUUUUUUAAUUGUGCUUAGCAGAUAUUUAAGAAUGUUAGCACAGGUCUUUGAAUAAACUUUGCUUCUAAGAGAAGUUACUAUUCAUAAUUAGGUAGAAAAGUCUUUGAAGAGGAACCUCUACUUCACUUUUUACACUGUGAACUGAGAAUGCUGUGUUCAGAGUGAUUACUGAAAACAUGGUUAAUACACUUCUUCCAUAUGAUAAUAAAAUGUUAUAAAUCUUA